GCAGUCCUAAACGCGGGGUAGCUCCGGGCUUCCGAGGGGGUGUGUCUCCCGCCUCUUUAACCUGGCAGGGGCGGUUCAAGUGGCCGGGGAAAUCAGCGAAUUGCAGGGUCAAGGGCUGGUGCUUUGAAAGAGAGGCGGAGGGGAGAGAGGGAUUUUCCCGUCCCCGCUGCGCUCUGUCCUCCAUUACUCCUUUUCUCGGCCCGCGGCCCGAACCCGCUGUGCGGUAGAGGCAGCCGGGUCCCUUUAAGGCCCAGCUGCGCCUGUGCCUUGGGCUCUCCUGACACGGCCCAUCCGGACCCUGAGGAGCCAGCGGGCCGCAAGCAAGUUGCUGGGCGGCGGUGGAGAUAGCGGCGGUGCUGGGAGGGGUAGGUGAGGGUCGCGAGGCUGCCUGAGCUUCUGAGUGAGCCUGGUGAUUUUGGGAACGCGGGACGGGCGACCUGCGGCGCCAGGAGCGGGGCCGAGGUACGGCGGCACGGCUGCAGCCUGGAUGGGAAGUUCAAGUUUACUGCGAAGUCCACCCAGCGUUCCGGAGGUGAGGGCGCCGCGCCAGGCCGGGCGGGAGGCAUUCUGAAGGCAAAUCCUGUUUAGACCCAGGCAAAGGUUCCUGGUGACCCAGGCUCUCAUGAGCAGAUUGUCCCUUAUCAUUCUCCUGAGGAUGUCUGGAGCUUCAGUGCUGUGUGCUCUUGGCCUCCACACUGGGGGUGCCACCAACUCCCACUGUCCAGGGCUUCUGGUGGACUCUCCGAGGCACCGAUGUAGAAACUUACCCAUUCAGUGCACCAAGAGCAGCUUCACAUGGUGUGGGCCGACAUGAAGAGCUGCCAGAUCCAACAGAAAUGUGAUUGAUAACAGUAAAGCCACACUCCUCAAGUGCCUGAAAUACCCCUCAUUGUCUUCUUCAGGUGGCAAGGGCUCUGGAACAGCCACAUAAAGGCUGAUGACUUCAGGGACAUGAGCAUGGGAUACCUGUCAUCACCACCACCAUGAAGUUGGGAUUCAGGAAGGAGUUUAAUCAUGUAAAGAAUCCUGUGACCAGUAUGAGCUUCUCUCAGGCCACACAGGGCACUCAAGUGAACAGGGUCAUGCCCUUGAAGAUAAGGAUGGUCAAACAAAAUAAUAUCAUACCUGGAGAAACUCAGAUCUUGCUAAGAUUUACUGGUUGGGAAUCCAAAGUUAAUGCCAAGAAGCAGCUGCCAGUUGGGAUCAAAUGUGAGCCUAUGGAUCAAGACGGUUACCUGGCACGCUGGCCACAAUCUACCUCACUCUUAUCAGAGUCUGAGCAGUGCUUUCAGCUCUGAGUUGAGGCACCUCGAACCUUGUUUUUGUGGUGAAGGAUCCUAAAGUGCUGUGGGGAGUGAUCACAUUUUUCACAACAUCCCUGACUCCACCUCUUCUGCCACAAACGUCAGCAUGGUGGUAUCAGCCGGCCCUUGGUCCAGCGAGAAGGCAGAGAUGAACAUUCUAGAAAUCAACGAGAAAUUGCGCCCCCAGUUGGCAGAGAACAAACAGCAGUUCAGAAACCUCAAAGAGAGAUGUUUUCUAACUCAACUGGCCGGCUUCCUGGCCAACCGACAGAAGAAAUACAAGUAUGAAGAGUGUAAAGACCUCAUAAAAUUUAUGCUGAGGAAUGAGCGACAGUUCAAGGAGGAGAAGCUUGCAGAGCAGCUCAAGCAAGCUGAGGAGCUCAGGCAAUAUAAAGUCCUGGUUCACUCUCAGGAACGAGAGCUGACCCAGUUAAGGGAGAAGUUACGGGAAGGGAGAGAUGCCUCCCGCUCAUUGAAUGAGCAUCUCCAGGCCCUCCUCACUCCGGAUGAGCCGGACAAGUCCCAGGGGCAGGACCUCCAAGAACAGCUGGCUGAGGGGUGUAGACUGGCACAGCACCUUGUCCAAAAGCUCAGCCCAGAAAAUGACGAAGAUGAGGAUGAAGAUGUUCAAGUUGAGGAGGAUGAGAAAGUACUGGAAUCAUCUGCCCCCAGGGAGGUGCAGAAGGCUGAAGAGAGCAAAGUCCCUGAGGACUCACUGGAGGAAUGUGCCAUCACUUGUUCAAAUAGCCACGGCCCUUGUGACUCCAUCCAGCCUCACAAGAACAUCAAAAUCACAUUUGAGGAAGACAAAGUCAACUCAUCUCUGGUUGUAGACAGAGAAUCCUCUCAUGAUGGAUGUCAGGAUGCUCUAAACAUUCUCCCAGUCCCUGGCCCCACCUCUUCUGCCACAAACGUCAGCAUGGUGGUAUCAGCCGGCCCUUUGUCCAGCGAGAAGGCAGAGAUGAACAUUCUAGAAAUCAAUGAGAAAUUGUGCCCCCAGCUGGCAGAGAAGAAACAGCAGUUCAGAAGCCUCAAAGAGAAAUGUUUUGUAACUCAAGUGGCCUGCUUCCUGGCCAAGCAGCAGAACAAAUACAAAUAUGAAGAGUGCAAAGACCUCAUAAAAUCUAUGCUGAGGAAUGAGCGACAGUUCAAGGAGGAGAAGCUUGCAGAGCAGCUGAAGCAAGCUGAGGAGCUCAGGCAAUAUAAAGUCCUGGUUCACUCUCAGGAACGAGAGCUGACCCAGUUAAGGGAGAAGUUACGGGAAGGGAGAGAUGCCUCCCGCUCAUUGAAUGAGCAUCUCCAGGCCCUCCUCACUCCGGAUGAGCCGGACAAGUCCCAGGGGCAGGACCUCCAAGAACAGCUGGCUGAGGGGUGUAGACUGGCACAGCACCUUGUCCAAAAGCUCAGCCCAGAAAAUGAUAACGAUGACGAUGAAGAUGUUCAAGUUGAGGUGGCUGAGAAAGUGCAGAAAUCGUCUUCCCCCAGGGAGAUGCAGAAGGCUGAAGAAAAGGAAGUCCCUGAGGACUCACUGGAGGAGUGUGCCAUCACUUGUUCAAAUAGCCAUGGCCCUUAUGACUCCAACCAGCCACAUAGAAAAACCAAAAUCACAUUUGAGGAAGACAAAGUCGACUCAACUCUCAUUGGCUCAUCCUCUCAUGUUGAAUGGGAGGAUGCUGUACACAUUAUCCCAGAAAAUGAAAGUGAUGAUGAGGAAGAGGAAGAAAAAGGGCCAGUGUCUCCCAGGAAUCUGCAGGAGUCUGAAGAGGAGGAAGUCCCCCAGGAGUCCUGGGAUGAAGGUUAUUCGACUCUCUCAAUUCCUCCUGAAAGGUUGGCCUCGUACCAGUCUUACAGCAGCACAUUUCACUCAUUAGAGGAACAGCAAGUCUGCAUGGCUGUUGACAUAGGCAGACAUCGGUGGGAUCAAGUGAAAAAGGAGGACCAAGAGGCAACAGGUCCCAGGCUCAGCAGGGAGCUGCUGGAUGAGAAAGAGCCUGAAGUCUUGCAGGACUCACUGGAUAGAUGUUAUUCAACUCCUUCAGUUUAUCUUGGACUGACUGACUCAUGCCAGCCCUACAGAAGUGCCUUUUACGUAUUGGAGCAACAGCGUAUUGGCUUGGCUGUUGACAUGGAUGAAAUUGAAAAGUACCAAGAAGUGGAAGAAGACCAAGACCCAUCAUGCCCCAGGCUCAGCAGGGAGCUGCUGGCUGAGAAAGAGCCUGAAGUCUUGCAGGACUCACUGGAUAGAUGUUAUUCGACUCCUUCAGGUUAUCUUGAACUGCCUGACUUAGGCCAGCCCUACAGAAGUGCUGUUUACUCAUUGGAGGAACAGUACCUUGGCUUGGCUCUUGACGUGGACAGAAUUAAAAAGGACCAAGAAGAGGAAGAAGACCAAGGCCCACCGUGCCCCAGGCUCAGCAGGGAGCUGCUGGAGGUAGUAGAGCCUGAAGUCUUGCAGGACUCACUGGAUGUUAUUCAACUCCUUCCAGUUGUCUUGAACAGCCUGACUCCUGCCAGCCCUACGGAAGUUCCUUUUAUGCAUUGGAGGAAAAACAUGUUGGCUUUUCUCUUGACGUGGGAGAAAUUGAAAAGAAGGGGAAGGGGAAGAAAAGAAGGGGAAGAAGAUCAAAGAAGAAAAGAAGAAGGGGAAGAAAAGAAGGGGAAGAAGAUCAAAACCCACCAUGCCCCAGGCUCAGCAGCGUGCUGAUGGAAGUGGAAGUGCCUGAAGUCUUACAGGACUCACUGGAUAGAUAUUAUUCGACUCCAUCAAUGUACUUUGAACUACCUGACUCAUUCCAGCACUACAGAAGUGUGUUUUACUCAUUUGAGGAACAGCACAUCAGCUUUGCCCUUGACAUGGACAAUAGGUUUUUUACUUUGACGGUGAGAAGUCUCCACCUGGUCUUCCAGAUGGGAGUCAUAUUCCCACAAUAAGCAGCCCUUACUAAGCCGAGAGGUGUCAUUCCUGCAGGCAGGACCUAUAGGCACCUGAAGAUUUGAAUGAAACUAUAGUUCCAUUUGGAAGCCCAGACAUAGGAUGGGUCAGUGGGCAUGGCUCUAUUCCUAUUCUCAGAGCAUGCCAGUGGCAACCUGUGCUCAGUCUGAAGACAAUGGACCCACGUUAGGUGUGACACGUUCACAUAACUGUGCAGCACAUGCCGGGAGUGAUCAGUCGGACAUUUUAAUUUGAACCACGUAUCUCUGGGUAGCUACAAAAUUCCUCAGGGAUUUCAUUUUGCAGGCAUGUCUCUGAGCUUCUAUACCUGCUCAAGGUCAGUGUCAUCUUUGUGUUUAGCUCAUCCAAAGGUGUUACCCUGGUUUCAAUGAACCUAACCUCAUUCUUUGUGUCUUCAGUGUUGGCUUGUUUUAGCUGAUCCAUCUGUAACACAGGAGGGAUCCUUGGCUGAGGAUUGUAUUUCAGAACCACCAACUGCUCUUGACAAUUGUUAACCCGCUAGGCUCCUUUGGUUAGAGAAGCCACAGUCCUUCAGCCUCCAAUUGGUGUCAGUACUUAGGAAGACCACAGCUAGAUGGACAAACAGCAUUGGGAGGCCUUAGCCCUGCUCCUCUCAAUUCCAUCCUGUAGAGAACAGGAGUCAGGAGCCGCUGGCAGGAGACAGCAUGUCACCCAGGACUCUGCCGGUGCAGAAUAUGAGCAAUGCCAUGUUCUUGCAGAAAACGCUUAGCCUGAGUUUCAUAGGAGGUAAUCACCAGACAACUGCAGAAUGUAGAACACUGAGCAGGACAACUGACCUGUCUCCUUCACAUAGUCCAUAUCACCACAAAUCACACAACAAAAAGGAGAAGAGAUAUUUUGGGUUGAAAAAAAGUAAAAAGAUAAUGUAGCUGCAUUUCUUUAGUUAUUUUGAACCCCAAAUAUUUCCUCAUCUUUUUGUUGUUGUCAUGGAUGGUGGUGACAUGGACUUGUUUAUAGAGGACAGGUCAGCUGUCUGGCUCAAUGAUCUACAUUCUGAAGUUGUCUGAAAAUGUCUUCAUAAUUAAAUUCAGCCUAAACUUUUUGACGGGAACACUGCAGAGACAAUGCUGUGAGUUUCCAACCUCAGCCCAUCUGCGGGCAGAGAAGGUCUAGUUUGUCCAACACCAUUAUGAUAUCAGGACUGGUUACUUGGUUAAGGAGGGGUCUAGGAGAUCUGUCCCUUUUAGAGACACCUUACUUAUAAUGAAGUACUUGGGAAAGUGGUUUUCAAGAGUAUAAAUAUCCUGUAUUCUAAUGAUCAUCCUCUAAACAUUUUAUCAUUUAUUAAUCCUCCCUGCCUGUGUCUAUUAUUAUAUUCAUAUCUCUACGCUGCAAAUUUUGGGUCUCAAUUUUUACUGUGCCUUUGUUUUUACUAGUGUCUGCUGUUGCAAAAAGAAGAAAACAUUCUUUGCCUGAGUUUUAAUUUUUGUCCAAAGUUAAUUUUAAUCUAUACAAUUAAAACCUUUUGCCUAUCA